CCACAGGAAACCACCACACAUUUCCUUAAAUUCAGGGUCCAGCUCACAUGGGAAAUACUUUCUGAGACUCAUGGACCUCCUGCACAAGAACAUGAAACACCUGUGGUUCUUUCUCCUCCUGGUGGCAGCUCCCAGAUGGGUCCUGUCCCAGGUGCAGCUGCAGGAGUCGGGCCCAGGACUGGUGAAGCCUUCGGAGACCCUGUCCCUCACCUGCGUUGUCUCUGGUGGCUCCAUCAGCAGUAGUAACUGGUGGAGCUGGGUCCGCCAGCCCCCAGGGAAGGGGCUGGAGUGGAUUGGGGAAAUCUAUCAUAGUGGGAGCCCCAACUACAACCCGUCCCUCAAGAGUCGAGUCACCAUAUCAGUAGACAAGUCCAAGAACCAGUUCUCCCUGAAGCUGAGCUCUGUGACCGCCGCGGACAGGGCCGUGUAUUACUGUGCGAGAGACACAGUGAGGGGAGGUGAGUGUGAGCCCAGACACAAACCUCCCUGCCAGGAGGCGGAGGGCGCGGACGCAGGUGCUGCUCAGGACCAGCAGGGGGCGCGGGGCCCACAGAGCAUGAGGCCGGGUCAGGAGCAGGGGCAGGGAGGGCGGGGCUUCCUCAUCUGCUCAGUGGUCUCCCUCCUCGCCAGCACCUCAGCUGUCCCCAGGGCUCCUCUUUCUUUAUUGUUUGUGGUUCUGCUUCCUCACAUCCUCACUGCAGCAUUCCCUUACAUCCUUGUCAUGCAUCUGUCCUCUGUGGGCGCCCAGGGCAGGUUACACAGGAAUUGCCUGAAGCUGGCCUCAGCUGAUGUGCUGAGACCACGGGUCAUGCACACGUAUGAUUCCAGGUCAUGCGGGCUCUACUGCAGGACAGACCUGUGUCCUGUGGGGCACAGCCACCUGCUGAUCCCGGGCCUCCUCUAA